CUUGCUAAGAGCAAACUUGAAGGUAUGGAUAAGGCCCUGAGUCAUCUUCCUGAGCUGAAUGAUAGUUAAGCUGAAUUUCAAUAACUAUAAUUUCUCUGCUGUGCAAUCAAAUACUAGAACUUCUUCCUUCGAACGCUAUAUCCCUAAUUCAAUAACAAGUAAACUGAAGCUCAGCAUGGUCUAGGAACUUUGUUACGUUAACACAGCAAGUGAGUGUUGCAGCCUGGAUCCAAAAAUCAGGCCUGGUAGACCUCAAAGUCCAGAUUAUUGACCUUUCUACCAUAAUGUAUGGAGGUAAGUUUGUGAAUUUAUUCAAAAAUCAGGCCUGGUCAACCUCAAAGUCCAAAUUAUUAACCUUUCUACCAUAAUGUAUGGAGCUAAGUUUGUGAAUUUUCAUAGUUUUAGGAUUUGAAGAUAAAAGAGGUGAAAAUUUGGAAAUGGUUUCUGGACUUUGAAUUUUGGCAAACAGCUAUGUGAUAAGUCCACCCUGCAGACCCACAACUUUUGGAAAUAACUCUACUGUGACCUUCAGUAGCAGAAGCUGCUCCUGGGGUGGUAGAACACAAGGAAAACACACACUAGUAAAAAUUUCAUGUGCCUUCUUUGUUCUGUACAUGUGUUUCUCUUGAUUAGUAUAUGGUAGUAUCCUCAAAUCAUAGUAACAAGUAUACUUUUUCCAGUGAAUUGCAUGUGUAUAUUAUUGUAUAGUAUAAAAGGCAAUAUUUCCAUUUAUUAUCAUCUGUGCUUUUCAAAGAAACUCUGUGAGUCCAAAAGGGCGAUAAUAGAAGCAACUGCCCUUUCUCUCCCCCGUUAAAUGCAACCCAAUGUCAAAGUCCGUAGCAUCCCCAAAUGAGUGUGUUAAAGGUGAGAAAUUCCCAGAGUCAAACUCAGUAGCAUCCUUGAAUGAGUGUAUUAAAGGUGAUAAAUUUAUUUUAUUUAUGUUCUUUUUAACCUGUGUUCUCAGAAACAGAGACUACUGUAUUUCAUCCUACCUUAGUCUUGCUUAGCAGUUUCUCUUCUCCUUUGAGGCUCUUUUAUUUUUAAAUCAUUGUUCAUAUCUUCUAAUUUCCCCUUUCUCCCAUUCUUUCCAUAUUUUUAAUCUUUUUUUAACUUUAUCUCUGUUCUGCUUUUUCUGUAUUUCAAAUUGAUCCAUAGACUUUAGAAAAAUGAGUUGAAUGCUGGCUGUAGGCUGUCUUAUCCCCAGCAAGAAACAUGUUGUAAAGUCUUAGUACCUUCCCACUGGAAGAUCAUUAGUCAUGGCUACUAUGUUUUUAAAUGAGAAUUGUUUUAAUUAUGCAUUUUAAAAUUAUUGGAAAACAUGAGGGAGAGGAAUGAACCAUAAGUAAUAAAGAUUAUUGACUUGAAGUUAAGACCUUACUAUGAUCUGGGAUUAUUAGUCUUACUUGUCAAUCAAGAACUAUCCACUUUCUAUUUGUUUGUGGGUAUCUAAUAUGGUUAUAUACACAGAAGUAAUGAUAAUUGAUAUGAAAAGGUCUCCUCCUGUUAUAUCAAUUUAGGUAUUUUUCACACAUUGUGUACCUCAUUCUUCUCCUAUUCAAUUUUCACUAAUUCCUAAAGGGUCAGGUCAAUGUCCUUGGCAUAACCUCCUCCACCUGUUCUUAAUGGCAAUUGUAUCUUCUGCCCUCCAAUAUCUAUAACACUUUUUUCUUUAAAACUCUUUGAAUGUUUAUCUUAAUACUCAUUUGAUAUAUAUUGUAUACCACAUAUGAUUGUUUGUUAUAUGUACAAUACAUGUUUUUUCAACUUUUUUUGGUUCUUUCCAUUUACAGGAAUUAGAGAAAGAACUAAUCAGUGUGAAGGAGAAUUGUCAGUAAAAUUACAAGAAAAGAUUGAGAUCAUAAUUGACCUUUGAGGAUAAUAAAAUUUAAAGACCAAAAGGAUGGACUUCACAGAAACAUGACCUUAGGUUGUUUUUGCAGUUGUAGUAACUGGUUAUAUGACCAACAAAAUAUGAAGAAUGGGUAAACAAAUUCUGAUAGUAAUGAUCAGUCACUUUGCAAAUAUAAAGUUACUAUUUACUACUGUAUUGUACAGGUUCAAUAAUCUUUGUGUACACAUUUUAUGUAUUUAUUGUCAGGCUGCUAUAUAAUUCAGUAUUUAUAAUAGAUACUAUGUAUAGCAAUCUAUGGUUAGUUUUGGUCUUAACCAGGAAAAAUCACUCUUUUGAGUUUUGCUGUUUUUACCAGAUUAUUUUUACUGGAUGAUUGCUCAUAUUAUUUGAUUAUUAUUGCAAUUUGUCUUUCUGGAAUAGGAAGCAAGAGGCCUGAAUUCUGGUUCCUAUUCUAUCAAUUGUGUGAAUUCUGGAAACUCAGUUUACUUUUCUGGGCCUCAUGGUUUUCAUCUGAAUGAUGACCAACUUGGAUAAAAUGGUCUUUAUAUAAUUCCAUAGGCAUUUCCCUUCCCAAGGGCUUGAGUCUUUUUCAACAAUUAUAGAGUUUUCCGGUCCCUCUUCCCAGUGCCUCAGCACCUUGCUAUUCAUGUUCAUCUGAUCAGUUGUUUGCAUGCUGACUUACAUUACCCUGAUGGGCAGUACCUGUGGCUGUUUCUGCUCCCUCACCCAGUCCAUAGGCUUCUGGUUGUAAAAAGUGUGCAUCUUGAGACUGUGGACAGUUAGCUCCAGAGGUGACAGUAUAAUCACUUCACGUAGAAGAGGAUAGAGAGAGACUCAUGCCAGUGGUGGUGAGCAAGUAUUAGAGAUAUGAUGUGUGCCUCUGUGAGUUUUGGGGUCUAAGAUAAAUUAUGGCACUAGGAAGAUGGUCCUUUGUGUCAGAAGAACUGGAGUUGUUGGUGCAAAAAAGUAUGAUGUCAGCAUAGCAGUUUUAUUUGUACCUCAGCAACUUCUAAAAUAAUCUCUAUUAAGUGUUUUCAGGAACUACUUUCUACUAUAGGAAAAUGAUUGAGGUGAGUAUCCAUCUGGACACAGAGAAAUAUAACACUGUUUUCUGCUCACCCUCCACUUCACAUAUAAAUACAAUAUGUGUUAAAGGACUAAAUUUCUAGUGUCACAGUUUGUACUUUAUAGUUUGAAGUCAAUAAGAAAGCUCAUAUACCUUCCUAAAAGUCACUUGUUAAUGUUUGAUAUUAAUCUAAUUUUAUCAUAAAUUAAAAGUAUAAAACUACAAAUUUCUUAAAGAUAAAAUAUCCGAAUGGAUUCAGUCAAAUUAAGCAUGAUAAUAUCAAAUAUCAGAAUAGGUUACCAUGCAGGAGGUACUGAGUACUUAAAAGGGUGGGGAAUGCAAUGAACAUAAAAGCUGGUACCAAGGGGAGGAGGAGACAGUGAUGAAUUAAAACAUUAUCUUAACUAAUCCAAGUGCUGGUCUUCAAUACUUUCAUGUGUAUAGACAAAGAGAAACUGCAGAGAUUUCUCACAACCUCUGUGUCCAUUUUAUGCAUGUAUCUUAGCAGAAACACUGGUGAAAUCCCUCCAAAACAUAUUUAUUAGGCAUGGAAAAAGCCUUACAUGACAGGUGGCAUAGGCUCCUUAUGAAAUCAUUGCAGGAUGGGAAGCCAUUUAGGGCUUCAUAAUUGUGAAAGAUUGUAUAGAAACUGAGGCACUUAAAUAGCAGUAAGCAUGAGAAAAUGUGGUAGAUAAUGGUGGUGAUUCUAUUUCUUGUGAAAGUCCACUUACUCUAGUCUGCUACAGUUGUGGGCUUUCCGAUUUCACAUACCCCAGUCUCUAUAUUCUCUCAAUCCACAGCCUACCUCAACUAAGUCCGUCCCAGGCACCUCUUACUGCAGUGAUAAUCCAUCUGUUAAUCAUGUUUUCCUCUUAUGUCUACUUUCUGUCAGAGAAUUGUGGGUGCAAACUGGGAAGGGAAGGAAAUUAUAAGAAUAUGUAUAAGUACAAAUGGAAUAUGUUGGAAAUGAGGAAUAGUUAAUAUCACAGGUCAUUUAAACACCUGAUGAAUUUCAUGGAUAGUCAGGAAUCUUGUUCUUACCUAAUCUGUUAAUUUUAGAUCAGACAUUACACUGAAAGUAUUGAUGAUGGGUUUAAAUCAGGUUGCAGCUCACAUGUUGUGAUAAUAUUAUGUUGAUUUUUUGUUUUUAAUAUGUGAGGAACAGAAUAACUGUAUACUAUUUAUUCAUAGUGACAUUGCAAUAUUGAUUUUAGUACAUAUUAUUAUCUUCAUAAUCACAAUUUCCUCCCCAUUUUCUUAGUUCUCAUAAUUUUAGCCACAGCCCAGUUGGCUGGACCAAUGGAUGGAGAGAAUCACUCAGUGGUAUCUGAGUUUUUGUUUCUGGGACUCACUCAUUCAUGGGAGAUCCAGCUCCUCCUCCUAGUGUUUUCCUCUGUGCUCUAUGUGGCAAGCAUUACUGGAAACAUCCUCAUUGUGUUUUCUGUGACCACUGACCCUCACUUACACUCCCCCAUGUACUUUCUACUGGCCAGUCUCUCCUUCAUUGACUUAGGAGCCUGCUCUGUCACUUCUCCCAAGAUGAUUUAUGACCUGUUCAGAAAGCGCAAAGUCAUCUCCUUUGGAGGCUGCAUCGCUCAAAUCUUCUUCAUCCACGUCGUUGGUGGUGUGGAGAUGGUGCUGCUCAUAGCCAUGGCCUUUGACAGAUAUGUGGCCCUAUGUAAGCCCCUCCACUAUCUGACCAUUAUGAGCCCAAGAAUGUGCCUUUCAUUUCUGGCUGUUGCCUGGACCCUUGGUGUCAGUCACUCCCUGUUCCAACUGGCAUUUCUUGUUAAUUUAGCCUUCUGUGGCCCUAAUGUGUUGGACAGCUUCUACUGUGACCUUCCUCGGCUUCUCAGACUAGCCUGUACCGACACCUACAGAUUGCAGUUCAUGGUCACUGUUAACAGUGGGUUUAUCUGUGUGGGUACUUUCUUCAUACUUCUAAUCUCCUACGUCUUCAUCCUGUUUACUGUUUGGAAACAUUCCUCAGGUGGUUCAUCCAAGGCCCUUUCCACUCUUUCAGCUCACAGCACAGUGGUCCUUUUGUUCUUUGGUCCACCCAUGUUUGUGUAUACACGGCCACACCCUAAUUCACAGAUGGACAAGUUUCUGGCUAUUUUUGAUGCAGUUCUCACUCCUUUUCUGAAUCCAGUUGUCUAUACAUUCAGGAAUAAGGAGAUGAAGGCAGCAAUAAAGAGAGUAUGCAAACAGCUAGUGAUUUACAAGAGGAUCUCAUAAAUGAUAUAAUAAGCCCUUCUCAUUAAACAUGAUAUGGCUUUAUGUUUCUUUCUUUGAUAUUUUAGAUUCAGGAACUAUGAGACAUUAUGUAUUGAUUUGAAUGUUAUUAGACCUGUAACAUAAUUCUUAUCUGAUGAAUAUAUGAUGAAUAUAUUCCUUGUUCAAAAUGAGUCAUAAAUUCAACACAUCUCUACAUCUAUAUUAUGCCCAUUUAAUUUCUUUCAGCAAUGUUUUGUAGUUUUUGGUGAACAGGUACUUUAUGCAUAUGUACUUUAUAUUUAUCUCUAAGUUUUAUAUUUCUGAUGCCCUUUUAAGUGACAUUUUUAUUUCAAUUUACAAUUGUUUAUUCUUAGCUUAUGGGCACAUAAUAGAUCUUUGUUUGACAUUAUAUCCUGUAAACUUGCAAAACUUAUAAGUUCCAUCAGUUUUUUAUAGGUUAUGUAGGAUUUUCUUUAUAGAUGAUUAUGUUGUCAGUGAAUAAAGACAUUUGCUUUUAAAAUUCUAGUAUGAAUUCACUAUAUUCAUUUUGUUGAAUGCUGAGUAGAAUUAGUUAGAGUAGACAUCUUUGACUUGUUCCUGUUAUGAAAUAUAUUAAAUAUUUCAUCAUUAAGUAUAAUGUUAGCUAUAAUUUUUUUCAUAGGUACUCUUUAACAGGCUGAGAAAGUUUUCUGUAUUCACAGUUUGCUGAAAAUUUCUUUUAUCUUUAGUCAGGAAUGGAUCUUGGAUUUUGUAAAGCUUUUUCGUUUCAGAAUCAGGGUAAUGCUGGCCCUUUAGAAUGAGUUGGGAAGCAUCUGCUCUUCUUAAAUUUUCUGCCAUAAUUUUGUAGAAUUCAUAUAAUUUUUUUCUUUAAAAAGGGAAGUACUUAAGUAUUUUUUCCCAUAAGUUACCCAUAAGUAAAUCUAAAGGAAAGUGGGAAACUUUGAUACGCAUUGGUUGCCCCCUGGUGGAGAUUUCUGGGUUCUUGAUUAUUUUAACACUGGAGAUAGAAUCUGGUGGAAUGACGUCAAUGCUACCGUGAUUAAGAGGUGUGUAGGAAAUGCUUCAUGUAAAAGAGAAAAUAGUCUUUAUGAGAAUCUGCCUGGUGGAAAGGAGUUGGUGCAACAAUAACAAUAUAAAUUAGUGAAAAAUUUUAAAUUGACAAAUAAUAAUUGUAUCUAUUUAUGGGGUACAAUGUAAUGUUUUGAUACAUGUUUAAAUUGUGGAAAGAUUAGGUCUAUCUUAUUGACAUACAUAUCUUUUUUGUGGUGAAAACAUUUAAAAUCUACUCUGUUAGUCAUUUUGAAACAUACAAUACCUUGUUAUUUAUUACAGUCACCAUUCUGUGCAAUAGUUCACUGAAACUUUGUCUAACUGAAACUUUGAACCCUUUUAUCAACAUCUACCUUUUCCAUGUCUACCCCCAACUACUAGCCUCUGAUAAUCACCAUUCCAUUCUCUACUUCUAUGAAUUCAACUUUUUUAGAUUCCACAUAUCAGUGAGAUCAUGUGAUAUUUGUCUUUUCGUGCCUGGCUUAUUUCACUUAGCGUGAUAUCUUCUGGGUUAAUUCAUGUUGUCACAUAUAUCAGGUUUUCCUUCCUAUUAAGGCUGAGUAGUAUUCCAUUGUAUAUAUACACUACAUUUUCUUCAUCCAUUUGUCAGUUGAUAGACACCUGUGUUGAUUUCAUAUUUGGGUAUUGUGAAUAAUGCUGCAAUGAACAUGAGCCUGGAGAUAUCUCUUCAGCAUAUUGACUUAAAUUCCUUUGGAUAUAUACAAGGAAGUGGGAUUGCUGGAUCAUAUAGUAAUUCUAGUUUUAGUUUUUUGAGU